CUUGGCUGGCCGGUGUAUGUCCGCUGGAUUGUGAGGCCCGGGAUCUGGGCUCCGCCGUGGUGCAGAAAUGCUGUGCCGGCUCGGCGGUCGGUGGCUGCGGCCGCUCCCUGCCCUGCAGCUUUGGGCUAGGGACCUGCCGCUUGCGCCGGUUCCUACGAGCGGCGCCAAGCGCCCCACUCUCCCAGUGUGGGCAGUGGCACCAGUCUCUGCAGUACAUGCGAACGGCUGGUACGAGGCCCUGGCCGCGUCUUCGCCGGUGCGGGUUGCGGAGGAAGUACUGCUCGGCGUGCACGCCGCCACGGGCCUGCCCUGGUGGGGCAGCAUUCUGCUCUCCACCGUGGCCUUACGGGGUGCUGUCACGCUGCCUUUGGCAGCCUACCAGCACUACAUCCUGGCCAAGGUGGAAAAUUUGCAGCCAGAAAUAAAAACUAUUGCCAGGCAUCUUAACCAAGAAGUUGCAGUUCGUGCAAAUCAGUUGGGGUGGUCCAAAAGAGAUGCCAGGCUCACUUAUCUAAAGAAUAUGAGGAGGCUAAUUUCAGAGCUAUAUGUGCGAGAUAACUGCCACCCUUUCAAAGCCACUGUGUUGGUUUGGAUUCAGCUUCCAAUGUGGAUCUUCAUGUCUUUUGCUCUCCGGAAUUUAAGCACGGGGGCAGCACAUUCAGAAGCAGGUUUUUCUGUUCAGGAACAGUUAGCUACUGGUGGAAUUCUGUGGUUUCCUGACCUCACUGCACCCGACUCCACUUGGAUUCUGCCUAUCUCUGUUGGCGUCAUCAAUUUGUUAAUAGUGGAGAUUUGUGCUCUACAAAAAAUUGGAAUGUCUCGUUUUCAGACGUAUAUUACGUACUUUGUCCGUGCAAUGUCGGUGUUGAUGAUACCAAUUGCUGCAACGGUACCCUCAGUGAUCAAUUGUUCUCUACUGGUUAUGCUCCAGCUUCGUGGGCCUUUCACAGAAUUUGCUGCUGCGUUCUCCUGGAUUUCGCCAACUUUGCCGAAUACCAUCGACCAAGUCAGAUUCAGAAACUCCUUAUAAAGACAUAUUUGCUGCCUUUAAUACCAAGUUCAUUUCAAGAAAAUGACAUAUUUUCCAAUAAUUUUGAAACAGUUGCAGGAGUCACUAUCAUCUAAAUGUAUUUAGACUUAGAAAUUCAGAUGUUACUUGAUUUCCUUUUAUUUAAAAUCAUUAACUUCAUGAAAUAUUGUAGGUUAAGAUGUAAUCCAGACCAGGCACAGUGGCUCAUGCCUGUAAUCCCAGCACUUUGGGAGGUCGAGGUGGGUGGAUCACCUGAGGUCUGGAGUUUGAGACCAGCCUGGCCAACAUGGUGAAACCCUGUCUGUACUAAAAUAACAAAAAAAUUAGCUGGGCUUAGUGGCAGGUGCCUGUAAUCCCAGCUACUUGGGAGGCUGAGGCAGGAGAAUCGCUUGAACCUGGAAUACAGAGGUUUCAGUGAGCUGAGAUCACCCCAUUGCACUCCAGCCUGGACAACAAGAGUGAAACGCUAUCAAAGAAAAAAAAAAGAUGUAAUCCAGAUAUAUUUGACAGUAAUUAAAAUCUUUUAAAUGUUAUAAAUGCAGUAUGUUUGUGAAAGUAUUAGAAUAGAACCAAAGUGCCUGUCUCUGUUUAUAAAGUUACAGUUUGUUAGAGCUACCAGAACUUUGGAGAAUAGGGUUAGCUACUGAAUGAUGGCAAGUUAAACUAAACAAUACUGCAUAUUACUGUUUUGUAAAAUAAGAGGAUCAGUGAGAUGAUUCAUGUUUUUUUUUUUUGAGAUGGAGUCUCACUGUGUCACCCAGGCUGGAGUGCAGUGGCGCAAUCUCAGCUCACUGCAACCUCCAUCUCCCGGAUUCCAGUGAUUUUCCUGCCUCAGCCUCCAAGUAUCUGGGAUUGCAGGUGCACACCACCACGCCCAGCUAAUUUUUGUAUUUUUAGUAGAGAUGGGGUUUCACCAUGUUGGACAGGCUGGUCUGGAACUGCUGACCUCAACUAAUCCACCCUCCUUGGCCUCCCAUAGUGCUGGGAUUACAGGCAUGAGCCACCUCACCCAGCAUUUUUUUUUUUUAAUUUUUUUAAUGAGACAGAGUCUCUCUCUGUCACCUAGGCUGGAGUGCAGUGGCACGAUCUCGGCUCACUGCAACCUCUGCCUCCCGUGUUCAAGCAAUUCUCCUACCUCAGCCUACUGGGUAGCUGGGACUACAGGGGUGCACCACCAUGCCCAGCUAAGUUUUGUAUUUUUAGUAGAGAUGGGAUUUCACCAUGUUGGCUAGGCUGGUCUUGAACUCCUGGCCUCAAGUGAUCUGCCCACCUUGGCCUCCCAAAGUGCUGGGAUUACAGGCGUGAGCCACUGUGCCCAGCUGAGAUGUUUCUUAUUAUUUUGGAGGUGGAGAGGAUUUUAGACCUCUUUGAGCAUCUGAAAAAAGGCUAUAUAUGUAUGGUUUUCUCUUCAGAAAAAUCUUAAGACUCACAAUACGGGGACUUCCUUGUUACCAGGAAGAUUUUCUGGCAAUUCCUAGUUAAUAAAUCUUAUUCUAAUGGAACAUACAUUGAUCUUGAGUUAAUGCGUGGUUGAAAAAAAAAGCGGGGGCAACUUGAAAUAUAUGCAGUAAAGUAGUCCAUGCAUACAAGUCCCUAACAUGGUAGAUGAUGUUGCCUCCCGGCCCUGCUCAGAAAGAAUACAAAAAGUGUACAUUCCUUUUUCUAUAAUUUAAGAAGUCUGGAAUACAGAGUGUAACACUGUGUACUGCUAGCACCCAAAGUGGAAAAUCUUAAGCAUUCAGAUUGUUUAGUCAAAGAAGAAAACCAGAAGGGCAGUUGCCUAUUGAGGUGAUUUUAAACCUGUUUAUUUGUAAGGAUUAAGUACCCUAAUAGGCUUAAACUAUGAUAGAGGUUUAAUACAGAAAAAAUUGACAGGUAUUAUAAAUUGUGGAUCCAGUUACUUGCUUAUUUAAUUUGUAAAGAGGUAAAAUUAGCUCUGGUUGAGAUAUCAAGUAUGGCAGGUAUUUGAGAAGGCUAUAAAUCAUAAUUUUCAUUUAGUUAAAAUAUGGACCUGAUUCUGGGAAACCCUAUCAUUCCAUCUCAAUGUUUUACAAUAAAAUAAAAACUAAAGUGAAAUUCAUUAGUCAUUUCUUUGAUUGAUGUCUCUUAAAUUUUAGUUCACCUGCUUAAUGAAGUUAUGACAUUUUUUAAUAGAAAAAAUGUACAGCAUACAGAGGUAAGAAUUCUGCUUCCCUGAGAAUUUAUUUUAGACAUAGAUGGUGGCAAUUAAGACUAGGUUCUUUUUUCAUACAAGUUCCUAGUCCUGGUUUCUGACUGUCCUAUUGGGGCAAUUGUGCUUUCCAACCACAUUGAAGGAAUUGAAAUAUCCUCAUUAUUUGUGGAUUUUAUAUUUGUAAAUUUGCCUCCUUGCUCAAAUCUAUCCAUAACCCCAGAACCAGUACUUGCACAAGUGCUUUUGAGCCAUUUGUAGGCAAAAAUGUGAGUCACCUCCCAACAGAAGUGAAACAAAUGGUACUCUGCCUUCUAGUUUCAGCUCUCAUACCGUAAACAUGUAUCCUUUUUGAGUCUACUUAGUCCCAUCUCUUCCUAAUUUCUGUUCUUUUUGUUGGUGAUUUUACUGUUUAAAAUGGCCUCCAAAUGCCCUGCUGGAGUGCUUUCUGAUGUUCCUAAGCUCAGGAAGGCUUAGGAGAAAAUAAGUAUAUUAGAUAAGCUUCAUUCAUGCACAAGUUAUAAUGCUGUUGGCAGAGAGUUCAGUGUUACUGAAUCAACAAUAUGUUGCAUUGUUCUGUUGACAAAAACAAAGCUUGCAGAAACCUAACCCUGUAUGUUUUCUAGGAGCAGUGAUUUGGUAUUCACUACUUCAGUGUUUGUGGACUUUAUGGAACAUAAGUACCACAAAUAAUGCAAAUUGACUAUAUUUGCAGCGUGUACAAUCAAGGAUGCAGAGGCAGAAAUGUGUGUGCAGCUUAGGUCAUAGUAAAAAGAGGAAAGAAUUUGAGGAAAAUUUUGCCAGUUACAUAUUACCUCUGGAAUAACUUUGCCUUUGCCGUGUGUGUUACUGUGUACACUCAGAUAUUUUUCUCAUAAUGGCCUUUGCCGUGUGUGUUACUGAGUGAGUACACUCAGAUAUUUUUCUCAUAAUGGCAUGAGGGAAAUCAGUCUCCUUUUCCCAUUGUGUUUGUCACUUUUGCUGAGACGCAAAAAAUAACGUGCUAUGAUAUUGUGAAAUAUGUAUUUGGUCUUUAUCCCCAAUCCCUGACAUCCAGCGGAAUCUGCAGAGUUAAGUGUCUUUUGUAUGCUCAUGUGAUGACUGGUGGCUGGGGGCCCCUAGAAAGUUUCAGGAUAGGGCAGAUCCUUGUGGCCAGGAGUUCCAGAUCAGCCUGGGCAACAUAGUGAGACCUUGUCUGUACAAAAAAGAAAGUAGGAAAAAACAUCUUUGGUUUUUCCUAUCUCCAGAUACUUCCUUUUCAAAUAAAUGAAUCUUCUUUCAUGUGCAUAAUUUACCUUGUUUACUGUGAGUCCCCUUGAUUUCAAAAUGUAUAUUUGUAUCUUUACAAAUGUAUAUUGUGCUUAGUUUCCUGUUGCUCUCCCAUUGUCAAACUUUCAAACUUGAAAUUUCUUUUCAAAUAUAUACAGGAAGUUUGAGAAUACAAGGCCCUUCCUCCAAGAUCUCAAAAUAAUUUCUCACAAGUGGGGGUUGCUGGGAUCUUGGGAUAAACCCAUGUAUAAAGAAAACUGGUGUAUUAUGAACUGAAGUGAAUCAGUUACCUGAACUUACCUGACUUCAGGAUGGUAAAUACUCUUGAUUUUUUUCUUCAGGCAGAUUUUUUUUAGUAAAGAGCAAAAAAUCUGUAUUGUAUUUCAGAAAAUUGCAAGUCUGUGGUCUUAUUUCUAACAGUUUGUCAUAGCCUGGAGCAGUUCCAGAACCUGAAUGAAGUCAGGGCUACAGAACAGGGAAUAUGCAUGCUCUUAAGACCCCUUGAUGUCUUGCUGUCUGGCUUGCCUAUAUCCCCUCAGUUGCUGAGGCUCUGCGCUGGGCCCUGCAGAGUUCAGGAAGGUUUUUGUCUCCUUAGAUGAGGACUGUAAUGUUUGUGUUACCCUUCCCCACAGGGGUGUUACCCACCCUUCUCGUCCUUACAGGAGAUCUGUUUUUCCUGUGGGUCUCAUUUUUGUCUCUAGGCCAGAUUCACUGUCUUAAUGAAUGCUUCUCAUUUCAAGAGUCAGGAAGGGAGACUCACUCCUGGAUCAAUUUAUAGUAUUUAUACCAUUAGGAUACCUGAGUUCAAAAGUAUAUUAAUAGAUAGAAUUGGCGUAUCUGAAAUGAUCCCAAAUUACUUUUCCCUGGGACCGUUAGAAGAGAAAACUGAACAAAUCCCAUCCUAGUCAGAUGUCCUAAGUGGGAAGAUGAGGCUUACAAAGGAAAACCAAAAUUCUUAAUUGCCACCCUGACAGAUAACCCAGGAGAAGGUGCAAAGCCUCAUUAAGAACCUCGAGGGAAAAGCCAAACUUGGGGAGAAGACUUUUCAGGUACCUUUAACAGCACUUAAGAGCUAAAGACCAUAUCUUCAUCUAAGAACCACCCAUUUACCCGUCCAAACCGAAAGAACAGACUUGGAGACCUGAAGAACAGUGGAAGCAAGACUUUUAAUGGCAGUCUUGCAAGAUUGGGUGUCUGGUGGGCAGGCACACCUGGGGCAGUUACAGCAGGUAAUUUAUCUCCUAGCACACAAGUCCUUCCCCCAGUUUCUGAUUGGUUAAGUACUAUGGGAUUACAGUCUUCCCAGACAUCGCGUAAGUUUCAUUAUCCCCCUUGUAAGGUUAUAUACCCCAUUCCCUUCCCCCCUUAAGUUUUGAUUUCCCAAUAACGAAACUUUCUUCCCUUUUAUGGGCUGACUCCUCCUCUACAUUCUGUUCGUUUAUUGUGACCUUCUAGGUGCAUGAGCAGUGCGGUUUGUUACAUACCAAGGCUGGCUGCCAGUGCUUAGAUUUAUCAUGCCUUGAAAAUGGACCAUUUAAAAUGUUUUCCCACAGUUCACAUCUCAGAGGAGGUACAGAGGUCCUCCUAGAUGACAUUGGGAAAAUUGUAGUUAGUGUGAAAAAAUGAGUGCCCAAAAAAACCUUGGUACCUUCUGUGUUUUGUUCCUAUUUUUUUUUUAUUGGACGCAUAAUCUGCUUAUAUUUUGCACCUAUUCUUAAAUCACACUUAUACCUUCAUAUUUUAUUCUUCUAAGAAUCCCAGGAAUCACCUUUUUUUUUUUUUUAGGAGUCACCUUUAAAAUUGCCUAUAUGUCAGAUUUAAGUCCCAGAAGCAGUAGGAAUGCAGACCCUAGAAAAAAAAUUAAAGAAUGUAGUUUAUUUUUUCCUCUGGGGUGUUAACUGCAGCUACUACAGAAUGCAGACUUUGGAAUUUCAGGCAUAACAUCUGAAACCAUGCAAGAAUUUAGAUUUCUGUAUUAAAGCUAAAUCUUCAUGUAAAUAUGGUGUAAAACAAUGCAUUAUCAUUAUAAACACUGUGCCUUACGAGCUGGUUCAAGCAGAACCCAGAUAAUUGGAAAUUAUAUGAAUUUAUAGAUUUUCCAUUUGAACCUUAUUAGUGUUGUUUAAACUUGUAAUAAUGGAUAUUUUCUAGUUAUCUGUUUUCUUUUUUUCAUACACUGUGAUGGUAUUUUAUGAAAUCAUUUGGUUUUGGGAAGUUGGAAUUUCCUAAAGCCACAGCAUUAAAGUCAGAUAAUUUUAUUUACCCAAAAGUUUCUGGAACGCUGUGGUUCUGUACUGUGUAUACAACUAAAAUAAGAAUAUAAAUUUAUAUAAAAAUAAAAAUACAACUAUAUAAGUAA